AGAAGUUUGAGUUUGUGUGCUUACUAGCAACCACUUUCAGCGUUUCUGCAAAGCUAGAGAAGGUAUCUUCUAAUUUAAAUGUCUUUAAGAAUUAUCUAUUGCGUAAUAUACUGUCAACAGGAGGUCAGUUUUAAAGGAAUACUACUGAUAGCCUGAAAGACUGUGGAAAAGAAAUUAUUUUUCCCCCUUACACACUGAUAGUUCUUGUAUUUGCAUUCCUGAAAUUCAUAUAUAUUUUUCAAAAAAAAAAAACCAUUGGAUUAGCAGCAAGAGAGUUGAAAAUGGCAGAAGUUGGGAAUGACUGCUAUUUCUUUUUUAAUUCCACAUGCAUAAAGGGUUCCCAGUGCCGAUUCCGACACUGUGAAGAGGCCCUUGGCAGUGACACUGUGUGCUCAUUAUGGAGAGAGAGGAAAUGUUUAGAUCCACUUUGCAGAUUUAGACACAUGGAAAUGCAGCAAAACUGCAGCAUUUCAUGCUUCUGGGAAACUCAGCCUCUUGGUUGUGUGAAGAUCAGCUGUAUCUUUUAUCACAGCAAACCUCGAAAUAUCAAUGGAUUAUUUUUGCCACCAAGUAGCAAUAUCACACUACAGAAAGAAAUUCAGGAAGGAAUUCCACUCCAGUCCCAGAGUCAAGAACCUCUGAAACCUCAGGAAAAUAUAUCACGACCCAUCCACCAUCCUUUAGUUUUAAAAACUAAUUUUGAGGAAGAAGAGGAAGUAGAUGAACAAAAUGAUGCUUCUAGUUUAUGGACAAAGACCCCUGAAGAAAUUGAAGAAAAAAGAGCAAUAAAGGAGAUGUGUUAUAAAUCUGGGGAAUACUACAGAUUUCAUACUCCUCCAGAUAUUUUGUCAUCAAAAAGCAUGACACCUACAGCAGAAAAACAGUUAGAAAAGCCUUUGGAAAAUGGCAGUGAAUUGCAAGAAGGAGAUAGUCUUACAGUUCCGACAAAACUUAGCCAAUAUGAAAGGCAAGGUGAAAUAAAAACAUCAUUGCAUGGGAAACCAAAGACUGACAUUGCUGCUUUUGAAAAUGGAGGAGGUGACUGUUAUGUUCCACAGAGGGUCAUAUUUCUUGGAGUCGAUGAAAGUGAAGCUUUAACUGAAGAGAAAGAAAUCACCAUAUCAAAAUGUUCAAAUACUAAAGUGAAUGAUGUCCAGCCAGUGAAGAAGCCUCAUUUUAAAGGUGUGAAGAAAAGAAAAUGGAUUUAUGAUGAACCACAGAACUUUCCUAACUCUGGAAUGCAGAGAGCAGUACAGGCCCCAAGACCCCAAAAUAAAAUGAGUUAUCACCGCAAUAAUAAAAAUCGAAAUGCGGAGAAUGCAUCCUAUAUCCACGUUCAAAGAGAUGCUGUCAGGACUGUCGCGUUGAAUGCACCUUCCCGCAGCAGGCCCACGCAUGGGUCCUACAAUAAAGUCCAUGCUAACAGGGAACCCAAACCCAACCUCAGUCCAGGUGAGGUCCUUUGUUGAUGUGGUUUACUCUUGUCUGUGGUUUGCAUUCCCAUGGAAUUUCUUGACAGCUUGGCUAAACUUCACUACUACUUACUCCCCUCUUCUUUACCCUGGCCAUCACCACCAUAGAAACUAGUGAGAGGAUUUCUUCCAUGUGCAGUCCUGCACAUGAUUUAAAGGAUAUGGAAGAAAACUCAUGUUGUGUGCAGAUGACUUCAGAUUGCACCUCCCUAGAGUUUUUUUCUCAGAGCACUGCACUUUGUUCCUCCAGGACAGCUUCAUGUCACUCAGGAGGACUGUUUUUGAAUGGCUGACAUUUUCUUGUUCCACUAACUGCAUUGUUCAAUUUUCACUGUCAGGCUAGUGCCUUGACUUUUCUGUAGGCCUUCAUGAUUAUUUUCUGAAAGGGUUGGUUUGGGGAUUAACUGCCAUAUUUUUGACAACCUCUCAUCUCUCUCACCAUGGAUAGAUUGCUUCUAAAUCAUUUCAUCAUGUAAUAGGCAAAGUCAUAGUAUAUGUCAGGAAGUACAAGGUUACAGGGGAGAAGAGAACCGAAUCUCUUUAUCUCUUUUUCUUCCUAUGUCUCAGAUGGAUUUUGUUCUUUUGAAGUUGGGUUUCAGUUCUCUAAACUUAACAAAAUGCUGCUCAAUUCUAUAUGAUUUCAUGUUUGUAUUUUUCUAAGUUCACGGUUUAGUUAGUGGAGUUCUGAAUAUUUUGAACUUAUGGAAACAUAAGACUAUAUCUUUCUAAGUUUCUUUUAUAAUUUAAUAAAUUUUUUAAAAUUAUGAGUACACAGUAGGUAUAUAUAUUUCUUUUACAAUUUAAAUAUACAUUAGCUUAUUUAAAUUAUUUUUCUUUUUGCUUUAAAAUAGAAUGAUAUAUGGAUGUGUAUUUGUAAAUAAGGAUAUUCUUAGGUGAAACGUGCUUUUAAUUUUAUUUAUUACUAUUAUCUUAUUUACUGAUAUUGUUAUUGUUAUUAUCAUUUUACUGCAACUGGAUGUCUGUGAAGAAUACAAUGAGUACUAGAAGAGCUGCCAAUGUCUAGGUUUGUGUGAAGGUGCCAGAAUUCAUACUCUAUAUUGCUUUUGCACCAUUAGUGCAAAUGUCAACACAAGAGAAAUGCAAAUUAUUGGUAUUACGGAUCAUGCUUUGAGAACACAGCUGCAUAGUAAUAUUUGAAAACACAAAUAUAACAUUGUUAGACAGUAGCAGAAAUGUAGAUAUGUCAGAGAAAAAUAAGUAUUUAAGGACCAGGUGAGGAUAUAAAUGCUUCGGCUAUCUGGGGCAGUGAGGUCGGUAUUGCAUCACACCAAUUACUGCGAACAUGGAAGUCACUUCAUGGAAGGACAUGGGACUUGGGCUGUACCUCAUAGUUUCACAGUUUUUAAAUAAAAGCUCUAAUAAACAUUAGCAGAAUUUAUGCAAAACUAUGAUGAAGUGAUGCAGUCAAAAUUUUUAUUACAUUUAGAUAUCAUACCCUCCUGUAGCUUACCCUUAUUUGAAGCAUUGAACAGCCAAUUAAGAAUCUGUCACCAUGCAACCUACUCAUCUGACAAAGGGCUAAUAUCCAGAAUCUACAGUGAACUCCAACAAAUUUACAAGAAACAAACAAACAACCCCAUCAAAAAGUGGGCAAAGUAUAUGAACAGACACUUCUCAAAAGAAGACAUUUAUGCAUCCAAAAGACACAUGAAAAAAUGCUCAUCAUCACUGGCCAUCAGAGAAAUGCAAAUCAAAACCACAACGAGAUACCAUCUCACACCAGUUAGAAUGGCAAUCAUUAAAAAGUCAGGAAACAACAGGUGCUGGAGAGGAUGUGGAGAAAUAGGAACACUUUUACACUGUUGGUGGGACUGUAAACUAGUUCAACCAUUGUGGAAGUCAGUGUGGCGAUUCCUCAGGGAUCUAGAACUAGAAAUACCAUUUGACCCAGCCAUCCCAUUACUGGGUAUAUACCAAAGGACUAUAAAUCAUGCUGUUAUAAAGACACAUGCACACGUAUGUUUAUUGUGGCACUAUUCACAAUAGCAAAGACUUGGAACCGACCCAAAUGUCCAACAAUGAUAGACUGGAUUAAGAAAAUGUGGCACAUAUACACCAUGGAAUACUAUGCAGCCAUAAAAAAUGAUGAGUUCAUGUCCUUUGUAGGGACAUGGAUGAAACUGGAAAUCAUCAUUCUCAGUAAACUAUCGCAAGGACAAAAAACCAAACACCGCAUGUUCUCACUCAUAGAUGGGAAUUGAACAAUGAGAACACAUGGACACAGGAAGGGGAACACCACACUCUGGGGACUGUUGUGGGGUGGGGGAAGGGGGAGGGAUAGCAUUAGGAGAUAUCCCAAUGCUAAAUGACGAGUUAAUGGGUGCAGCACACCAGCAUGGCACAUGUAUACAUAUGUAACUAACCUGCACAUUGUGCACAUGUACCCUAAAACUUAAAGUAUAAUAAUAAUAAAAAAAA